GAACCCACAGCCUUCCCCUCGAUUUGUCCUCUUGCUCCUUCCUGCUAGGACAGCAGGGCUUCUCGUACACAUGCUGUAGCGGGCACUGCCUUGGCAGGAGGAUUUGGGGCUUCCACAUAUCCUGUUCUCAAGAUUGUAGCAUCUCAGUACUCUAGAGCCCAGUACCUGACAUCAAGGAUGUCUGGAGCUUCCUUUUAAGGAAAGAAAAGAUCAGCAAACUUGCCUGUUCCCGUUUACACUUCCACCACCAGUUCGUGAGAGUUCCUGUUCUGCAUCCUCAACACUAGUAUUAAGUGAGAGUUCCUGUUCUGCAUCCUCAACGCUAGUAUUAAGUGCACUGGCCUUUAGUCUGUUAAAAAGCAUACAAUGGCUACAGAUGUUCAAUUGGCUGAUUAUCCACUGAUGAGUCCAAAGGCUGAGCUGAAACUGGAGAAGAAGUCAGGGCGCAAGCCAAGGAGCCCCAGGGACAGUGGGCCACAGAAAGAACUGGUGAUCCCAGGGAUUGUGGAUUUCGAGCGGAUCCGCCGGGCAUUGAGGACCCCAAAGCCCCAAACCCCUGGCACCUACUGCUUUGGACGCCUCAGUCACCACUCCUUCUUCUCCCGGCACCACCCACACCCCCAGCACGUGACCCACAUCCAAGAUCUCACCGGGAAGCCUGUCUGUGUCGUCAGGGAUUUUCCAGCCCCCUUGCCUGAGUCAACUGUCUUUUCCGGCUGUCAAAUGGGGAUACCCACCAUCUCUGUCCCCAUUGGAGACCCACAGUCUAAUCGGAACCCCCAGCUUUCUUCUGAAGCCUGGAAGAAGGAGUUGAAGGAGCUAGCUUCCCGGGUGGCCUUCCUCACCAAGGAGGAUGAACUGAAGAAGAAAGAGGAUACUACCAGUCUUAAUUGGAAUUGCAAGAGCAGGAGGCCCCAGGCACCAGGCCUCUCUGGGACAGACCUGGGGGCAGCUGAGCUGGGAAUUAAGAAGGAGCAGAAGGAGGAGCCUCUGCGGGAGCAGGGGGCAAAGUACUCAGCAGAGACUGGGAGGCUCAUCCCCGCUUCCACCCGGGCUGUCGGCCGCCGCAGAUCUCACCAGGGCCAGCAGAGUCAGUCUUCCAGCAGACAUGAAGGAGUCCAGGCUUUCCUCCUUCAGGAUCAGGAGCUGCUGGUCCUGGAGCUCCUGUGUCGGAUCCUGGAAACAGACUUGCUAAGCGCAAUCCAGUUCUGGCUGCUCUACGCUCCGCCCAAGGAAAAAGACCUCGCUCUGGGACUCCUGCAGACAGCAGUGGCUCAGCUCCUUCCCCAGCCCCUAGUCUCCAUCCCUACAGAAAAGCUCCUAAGCCAGCUUCCAGAAGUGCAUGAACCUCCUCAAGAGAAGCAAGAGCCACCCUGCAGGUGGGCCCCGCACCCCGCCCUGCCCUUCUGCAGCCUUCUGUCCUCCCAGGUUUCCAGCAUGACCUUCCCAGCCCCUUCUUUGUAUUUGGUCACAGUCAAUCCCCGAAGAAAACGAAGAUAUCACCUUUUACAAAAAGCGAAAAACCAGCACCCACAAUGUGCUGAACUCUGGGGAUCAGUGAGGAAGAAUUCAGACAAGUUCCUGCUGUCACGGAACUUACAUCCCAGCAAGGAGGAAUACAGACAACAAAUUAAAACACCUGGGGAGGAGUGGAGACAGAUACUACCAUCAAAGGUCCAGAGUGCCUGGCAGAGAGGCACAGAGUAGGCAUCUCAUUGAUAUUUGUUACUUGGAUGUUGAAAGAAGAGAGGUUGGAUUCCAUUCGCUCCAUUCCUCUCAGGUUGGAUUCCCUCCUCGGUCACCAGCAGAGCUGAGAGCAGGAGCUGGGCUUGACUCAGACCUUCCCCUCAGCACUCACACAUCCACCUGCAGCUCCCAGGUGGGGGCCCCACCUUCCCGGUCCUCUCCUGCCUGCUGUCUCUCCUCCCACUAGAGUACAUUGGAGAAGCUCAAGUCCUCCAGAUGCAUUCAAGCCAGAACACAGAGAAGAAGACAUCGAAGCCGAGGGCAGAGAGCUGAGGGGCCCUAACACUUGCACCUGCCUUGCUCAAGAGCAGCCCCAAGGGUUCAGGGGUGUUUCUGUCUCCACCACCUUCACAGCAGUACCUGAUUCCCUACCGUGAAAACUCUUACUAAAUAAAACCGUCUUCCCUGAGA